CGUUGUGGAGAGAGCUCAGACACCCAACAGGCCCUGCCAUCCCGGUGGGCGUGGACGUACAGGUGGAGAGCCUGGACAGCAUCUCCGAGGUGGACAUGGUAUGCAGCGGCCUCCAGUGACACAGCGUGAGAGCCUGUAGUGUAGUGGGCCUCGGUGGUGCAGGCUGUGCCUGUGUGGGCAGAGCGGGAGCUGGAGGUGAUAAAAUGGGCGCUUGGAAGUCGGCCCUGGAGCAGUAAAAUCUAAAGCGGGCAUUCUCGCUGCGUGGGUAAAAAUAACCUAAGGAGUUGGUUAAAUGUGGGUUUCUGGGCCCCAUUUCACACUUCCUGAUUCAGAAUCUCUGGGAGUGAUACUUUGCAUUUUCAACACACUCCACAAAUAAUGCAAGUGAUCAGGCGAACCACACCUGGUGGGGUACUGGAGGUGGACAGUUUCAGGCUGAAAUUUUGCAGCUUUCUGAUGUUCAGUUCCUGCUGCAAGUGCAGUCCCCCUACUCACUUUGUGGCAGUGUCCCCCACUCCAUGUCUACCCCAAUUCUACCACCACAGGCCUGGGUGUCCUGCAAGGCUCACAGUGGAGAGGUGUGCCCCCCACCCCAGGGCCCCAGCCUCCUCUCUUCCUUCUUCUGUAUGCCUCUCUUUCAGUUUGCAAACUUCCUCUUUCUUCUGCCUCAGGGAUCUUGAGCAUGCUUCAGCUCUGGCCCUCCCCAUAGCUAUCUCCUUCUUAUCCUUCAGGACUUAGCUAAAAUGAGACUUCUUCAAAGAGGCUUCCCUGACCUCCUGAUCUAAAGAAUUUCUGUUUUUUCUUCAUAGCCUACAUCAUCAUUUAUAAUUGUGCUAGAUAUUUAUUUGGGGAGUUUUCUUAUAUAUUGGUUGUCUUCCAUGCUUGACUAUAAGCUCCAUGAAUGCAGGGACUCAUGUUUUUCUUUACCCCAAUAUCUCCAAGUCUAGUCCAGUGUGGUCCCCCAGGGGCCCUGAAAAUGUGUGGAAUAAAUAAAAGUCGGGGAGGCUCCACUUGCCAGCACUGCAUCCCACUUGCAAUGCUGUCAUCUGCCCUUGAAGAGUGGGAACGCCCCUUGCUCCUAACGGACCCAGCAUGGCAGAGCUGAUAUGAUUGAUACUGAGGUUGUACACCCCCCAUAGCUCCAGCACCUGGUAAAAUAUGGGGCCCAGGUGUGAAAGGUGCAGGUAUGACAGUUUCCAAGAUGCUAGAUUUUACAUUGCCAGCCCCUUUGGAUAUCCAACAGCUGAGCCCAGUUCCAGAACCAGCUGUGUCUAGAACAGCCUGGCUGCCCUAGACUGAAUCAACCCAGAUGUCUGUGCUGAGUGUGAAGACUUUGUCCUGUGUGGCUCAGGAUCACAGGGAGAGGUAUCUAGAAUGACCUGCCUCUCACAGAGCAACCACCAACCUGUGGGAAGGCAGGUGGACUCCAGCAGUAGGUAGGUAACAUCCAAGGUAGCCAUACACAGCUGGUGUUUGUGAAUCUGCACUUCCCCUGGGCAAUGGCCCUCAGAGCCUGCUCUUCAGCUUUGUGACCGAGAAGGGAAAUAGCCAGAAGGGGCAUUUGGCUGGUCUCUUCCUACUCAGGUAUUGGCUGCUCUCCGUGUGUGUGGAGGGGGAGUUCCUGGCAGCUGCUGAUGCACUGGGAGCCAGGAUCAGUCUAGGGACAGACUCUCAUGCAUGCACUAUCCCAGUGCUCACUCAUUCUUUCCUCUCUUCCUGGGGCUCCCUCUGGGCCCACCACAACCACGAACUCUUUCCAGCCUUCCUCCACCCAGAAGAGGAUCUUUUGGGCAGUUAUUUUUCCAUUUGCACCUGUGUCAGCUUUGGCUAUGGGGAAGGACCAAACUCUUAAGGAAUCAACCAUGCAGGCAAGGAGACACUUUUGAACAAGGACUUCACUAUGACCCUGUACCUGCGGCAUUACUGGAAGGAUGAGAGGCUAGCUUUCUCCAGCGCCAGCAACAAGAGCAUGACCUUCGAUGGCCGGCUGGUGAAGAAGAUCUGGGUCCCUGAUGUCUUCUUUGUUCACUCCAAAAGAUCGUUCACUCAUGACACCACCACUGACAACAUCAUGCUGAGGGUGUUCCCAGAUGGACACGUGCUGUACAGCAUGAGGAUUACGGUCACUGCCAUGUGCAACAUGGACUUCAGCCACUUUCCCCUGGACUCCCAGACCUGUUCUUUGGAGCUGGAGAGCUAUGCCUAUACAGAUGAAGAUCUAAUGCUGUACUGGAAGAAUGGGGAUGAAUCCCUAAAAACAGAUGAGAAGAUCUCCUUGUCUCAGUUUCUGAUUCAGAAAUUUCACACAACUUCCAGGCUGGCCUUCUACAGCAGCACUGGCUGGUACAACCGUCUGUACAUUAACUUCACGUUGCGUCGCCACAUCUUCUUCUUCUUGCUCCAAACAUAUUUCCCUGCCACUCUGAUGGUCAUGCUGUCCUGGGUGUCCUUCUGGAUCGACCGCAGAGCUGUGCCUGCCAGAGUUUCACUGGGUAUCACGACGGUGCUGACCAUGACCACCAUCAUCACGGGCGUGAAUGCCUCCAUGCCGCGCGUCUCCUACGUCAAGGCCGUGGACAUCUACCUCUGGGUCAGCUUUGUGUUCGUGUUCCUCUCGGUGCUGGAGUAUGCGGCUGUCAACUACCUGACCACCGUGCAGGAGCGCAAGGAACGGAAGCUGCGGGAGAAGUUCCCGUGCAUGUGUGGAAUGCUUCAUUCAAAAACCAUGAUGCUGGAUGGAAGCUACAGUGAGUCUGAGGCCAACAGCCUGGCUGGGUACCCCAGAAGCCAUAUCCUGACAGAAGAAGAAAGGCAAGACAAAAUAGUGGUCCACCUGGGCCUGAGUGGUGAAGCCAACGCUGCCAGAAAGAAGGGGCUUCUGAAGGGCCAGACGGGUUUUCGUAUCUUCCAGAAUACCCAUGCCAUUGACAAAUACUCUAGGUUGAUAUUCCCUGCCUCCUACAUAUUUUUCAACUUAAUUUAUUGGUCAGUGUUUUCCUAGGGGCUCCAAGGCUGUUCCUAGAAGAGGGCAUAGACAUCGAGGGGGCCUGGCCAGUCAUUGACAGACGGACUUGUUGACCACACGCCCCUCACCAAACAAUGCAGCAGCUACUGGACCACCCUGAGCAGCACUCAUCUCUCAGAGAAGCCCAGGAGCCUUCCAGCUGCCCUGACCCCAGACCCCGUGGGGCUGCUCCAUGUUCAUGCUGUCUCGCGUCACACUUCACAUCUCUCUGGGACCUUCUGUUCUUGUGUGUGAACUAAUUCACAAGAACUCCCCUCCUAUAAACAAGGAUUCAAAUGCCUCCUAGACAUUCUUAGACCCUCAGAUUGCCUAGGAGUCAGUUGUGGAGGGAAAAGGAAAAACUGAAGUACAAGCUUAGGGGCAUUCUGGAUAGGAGAUAGGAAAUUAAGAACAAAAAACACCCUGUAAACCCAUUGAACUUGAUUAAGUGCCUACCUAGAAGGGAAAAGAGCUGAGAUCCCAGACAGGAAAUGAUUUGGCCUGUGGGAGUAUGGCAACCCACAGGAUUCUGCAAUAUUAGAGGAGAUUAUUCAUUUAUCCAUCCAUUCAACCAUUCAUUAAAUAUUGAGGUCCCACUCUGUGCCAGGUACGGUAGAAAUGAGAAAAUAGUCUCUUUCCUUAGAGAUCUUCUCUAAGUUGUGCUCAUUCUACAUAUGGCAUGAUGUACUUCUGCUCUUUCCCCUCCUUCAACCCCGCUUACCCCACAGACCCAUUCUGUUUGCUGUUGCUUUUACUCUUAGGCAUAUAAGGCAGGGUCCAGGAGAGGCCAGGUCCAGAACUUUCAACUAUCCUCCUCCAGUGAAGUUACACAGAUAGCACUAAUUUUGCCCAGCAAUGACAUGUAGCAAUGUGCAUGGAGUAUUGCCAGCCAGAGAAACUUACCCAGGCUCACCACGGUGUACAGUUUUUUUAUUGGGGUCGGUCAUGGAUUUAUAGCUGAUUGCCCACAUGGCUGACUUUAGUCUUUUGCCCCUCCAGAGGUUAAGCUGGUACCUUGAGGUCCAGGGCACCUAUCAUAAAUCACAUUGUUGGCAUAGACUAUCUGGUGUGGCCCAAGGCCCCAGUAGACAAAGACCCUUCUAUCUCACAGGACAUUCCAAGGGCAUAGAGGUUGCUUCCUAGUAAAGGUUAGUCCUUUACUACACAGCAACUCUUGUCAAUUCCCUAUUGUUAAUGUUAAUUGCGGUGUUACUAUUAUAUAUUCAGGCAAUAAACAUUUUAAAGUAUCUCUGCACUAGGUACAUUGGGGUCCAAAUUAAGAAUAAGAGUAGUCGAAGCUCUCAGAGAAGGAACUAGUAAAGGAAAUACCACACAAAUAUCUAUAAUAUAAGAUUAAGAGUGUUUAGUGCCUCAGUAAUAGUUCAGUGUGAGAUGGGAAUUCCAAGGGAGGAAAAACAGUCCCACCAGGGAGACAGACCUCAUGGAGAAAGCAGCCCUGAGAUGCCCCUUGAAGGUCAGGAUUUUAAGAAGAAGAAAUGGAGCAGAAUGCAUCCUAGAUCUGGGCUGUCUCAUAUGGUAGCCACUAGCCACAUGUCUAUUUAAAUUUAAAUUAGUAAAAAUUAAAAAUAUUAGCCAGGUGUGGUGGUGUGUGCCUGGGGUUCUAGCUACUCAGGAGGCUGAGGCGGGAGGAUUGCUUGAGCCCAGGAAUUCCAGGCUGCCGUGAGCUGUGAUCAAGCCACUGCAGUCCAGCCUGAGUGACAGAGCGAGACCCUAUCUCUAAAAUAAUAAUUAUUAUUAUUUAAAUUAGUUGAAGUUAAAUAAAAUUGAAAACUCAGUUCCUUGGUUACACCAUCCACACUCAAGUGGGCUUAGUAAGCACAGUUGCUAGUAGCUACUGCACUGGGCUGGGCAGCCUAAAGACCAGGAAGCUCUACCAGCCAAGAGACCAGCUUGAGCGGACGCAUGGGGAGAAUGGGAAGGUUUGCCAUUGCAGAGAACAGGGUUUGUGGGCAAGUCAUUCAUUUUGGCAGGAUCCUAGGCUGUGAUAAGAGGAGGUGAGCGACUAGCUUUUUCCACAACACUAGGGAUCAAGGCAGGUCCCCACCAUGCCGGUGCUUAUGAGGACAGCUUCCCCACUAUGGAGUUGCUGGACCCAAGACUACUAGAUUUCCCAGUCUCACAGACCAAUGAAGAACAAAAAUGCAUAAAUAUGGGUAAUUGGGUGGUACAGGGCAUCUGGACUUGUUUAGAAACCUUUUUUUCUUUUCUGAGACAGAGUUUCACUCUUGUUGCUCAGGCUGGAGUGCAAUGGCUUGAUCUUGGCUCACCACAACCUCUGCCUCCCGGGUUCAAGCAAUUCUCCUGCCUCAGCCCUGGAGUAGCUGGGAUUACAGGCAUGCGCCACCAUGCCUGGCUAACUUUUGUAUUUUUUAGUAGAGAUGGGGUUUCUCCAUGUUAGUCAGCCUGGUCUUGAACUCCUGACCUCAGGUGAUCCGCCUGCCUCAGCCUCCCAAAGUGCUGUGAUUACAGGCGUGAGCCACCACACCCGGCCAGAAACCUUUUAUCUAUAGAGACUCUCCCAGGCCACAGUGCUGCUCGAAGAAUGAUAAUUCUAUUGUCAUUAAAUAUAUCAUAUUGCUUUGCUUGUAAGUCUUAUUUAAUUCCAACCCUUCUCUGCUUCUGACUGCAUUGUUUUCAUGCAUUAUGGCUCAUAUAACAUAGUUGCCUGUUCACAAAUUAAAACAAAUAUUUAUUUUUGCUAGCUUCUAUGUUAAACUGGAGUUAAUUCUAUAGCAGACAUAUUUAGAAUCAUAAACAGUGUUUUAUCAUGCAGGGCCAUGAUACAAUGACACCAUUGUAUUUAGCAUUGCCUUAUUACAGUAUACUAGUCUGACACUACUUGAGAAAAGUAGGAAAUUUAAAGAGGUAAAGUGGAGACAACAUUGGUAGGAGUAGAAAACAGGAACUAAGGAAAUAGUGAGAACAUGGGAUGAUUCACCCUGGAGGCAGGAAGACAGAGAAGCAAACACAAUUGUUAUCAGGAAUGCAUGAAUGAUACUUUACUUCACUGAAUCUAAGACAUGGUGAAAUGUAAGAUGCACCCAUAUUUUAUGUACUGAGAAAAAAUACUAACAAUCAAAUUCUGGAAUGCCAAUGAUUAUAAUAUGAAUCCUGAUUUCACCAAUAUGAAACUGUGAAAAAAUGUUAAUGUUACAAUAAAAGAAAUGGGUUUUAUACAAAAA